GCUGCUCUCUGGUCUCUGGAUAUGAGGCAGGAGGGCUUGGGGACAACUGUGGGGACAUGGCCCAGAUGAUCUGAUCCUGGCAGUAGUGACUGUUGGGGACCAGGAUGCUGGCAGGUCAACUCGAGGCCAGGGACCCCAAAGAGGGCACCCACCCAGAGGACCCGUGCCCAGGAGCUGGGGCUGUCAUGGAGAAGACAGCUGUGGCAGCCGAGGUUCUCACGGAGGACUGCAACACUGGGGAGAUGCCACCAUUACAGCAGCAGAUCAUCAGACUCCACCAAGAGCUUGGGAGACAGAAGUCUCUGUGGGCUGAUGUUCAUGGAAAACUCCGGAGUCAUAUAGAUGCUUUGAGGGAGCAGAACAUGGAGCUCCGAGAAAAGCUGAGAGCUCUGCAGCUGCAGCGGUGGAAAGCCAGGAAGAAAUCUGCAGCGUCCCCACACGCGGGGCAAGAAUCGCACACUCUGGCAUUGGAACCUGCUUUUGGAAAAAUUUCACCUCUGUCAGCUGAUGAAGAGACAAUACCCAAAUACGCUGGCCACAAGAAUCAGAGUGCCACUCUCCUGGGACAAAGAUCGUCAUCUAACAAUUCAGCUCCUCCAAAGCCAAUGAGUUUAAAGAUAGAAAGAAUUAGCUCGUGGAAAACACCACCACAGGAAAAUAGAGAUAAAAAUCUUUCCAGGAGACGUCAAGACAGAAGAGCAACACCUACUGGAAGGCCAACUCCCUGUGCAGAGAGACGGGGGGGUGUCUGAAGAUGGAAAGGUGGCCUCGGACACCUGUGUCACUCUACACUGGCCCCUUGGAAAAUUCAGAUUCAGAUAAAGUUCCACUUAGGUCUAAUAAAAGUACUCAAUUUGUUAUUCAAAAUAGACCUAGUAAUUUAUUAAACUAAUUAUGUUUCUAUAGAUAAAAACUUGAAGUUCUUCAGACAUGUCUCUAAUGCUAUAAAAGCAAACAACUUGGAUUGGGUUUUAUAAAUCAGUUGCUUUCCUGAGCUCUGUAGUUGGUAUAUUUCUGCAGAGUCUUUAAAAAAAUUAACCCACCUUGUAGUAUGGAGUGUCGGGCUGUUGGGUGAGCCCUGGGGUCUUGCUGGAAAUCGAGGAUGGCUGAAGAUGGCUUUGUGCUCCCAGCCUUUGGGCUCAAGGCAUUGCCCGCUCCAGGGACCUUGUGACAAGGCGGGCCUGUGACUGUCAUUGCCCCAGGCUAUGCAUCCAUCUUCCCGAAGUCUGCAAAACUUGAGUGGCAGAAAAUCACCAGUGCAGGCUUCCCAGGCCGCCAUGCUGCAGGAGCAGAUGGCAGCAGCCGGAGGAGCUGGUGAGCAGAGUUGGGGACUCCUGUUUCUAUGCUCCCCGUGAAAUGCGGGGCUUUCUCGUGGAUACGCGUGAGCAGAACAUCUUACUAUGGCAAGGACAUGUCCUUCCUGGAGCUGCCUAAUUUGUGGCCACUUUUUGUCUGAUUCCCUCGUUGGGUCCUCACCUGUGAGACUUGCCAACACCCCCAGCCCUCCACCCCACACACAGCCCACAUGCCGGUCUCCAGGGGCCGUGACUGGAGAUUCCGAAUCCUAGCGGUCACUUCCCUCUGAGCACACUCCCAGCAGAAGGCGUGUGGCUGGGGCUAGAUGCACUUGGGUGCUUUGUUCCCCUUUCUCCAUUUGCCAGCCCAUGGCAUUGCUGCCACCCUGAUGGAGCGCCCUCUCAUCUGGCACCUUCCUGGCCUCUUUCCCAGGCCCCAGUUCUGUCCAUGCAGCUGUGGGUGCUUCCUGCAUUGCGGGUCUCACGGGGAGGAGACGAGAGUGCCCCUGGUUGAGUCAGGAAAGAAUUCUAUCUUCACGUCGCUGCCAGCAAAUGACCACAGCAGCUUCACGACCUCUGCAGGAACCUAUCUUGGUAAAGAAACGGGGCCUAUGUGGUGGCCGAGCCUCAGGUGUGGCCGAGCUUCAGGUGUGGCCCUUAUGCACAGCACAGCCCAAGCCUGUGGGCACCACUCGCCCUGGGCUGCCUGGCACCUGGACUCCUUCCCAUCCUUGGCCGAGGUCUGCGUGGCCCUUCAGGGCCGAAUCUGACACUGUCUUCCUCCUGAGUCUGCCCCCCGGGCUUCCUGCCCACCCCCAGGCUGUUUCAUGGCCUCUGCAGGGAGCUUCGUAGAGGUGAGGCUGGUGCCAUCUGUCUGCUUCAGACCACCUCAGGCUCUGCGUGCCCUCACAGUCCCCUCUGCACUUCUCUGUGGGGCAGGGAAGCCCUUCCCAUCAGGUCUGCUCCAGCCUGGCUACCUUGUUCCUGCUGUCCCCUCCCCUUCAGGCCCCCGGACAAGACUUCAGUGUACUUGCUGGUGCCGGGCAGAAUGGGGGACCUUGCCUCUCACACACACCUGCUAGUAUCUCCGCAACCUCCAGGCAUCAUCUCAGCUGACAGUGACGCCAUCCUGGGGAAGCUCCCCUGACUCCUGGCUCUCCUGGAAGCCUGUGGUGCUCCUUCACAAUGGCCCGUGGCCCUUCAUAGGUCCCGUAAGCCAGUGUCACAGGGAUUCGGCUUUUCUCUUCUGUGUUUGCCUGCUGCGGGACUGUGAGCAGCUUCAGGGCCAAGACAGUGCCUUUCCAUCCGUGAAUCUCCUGAUCCAUCAGAAUACUCGAAAGAGAAAUACCGACUGAGUGUAUUCAUUAAAGAAUUAAUGUUCCUUACAGGAUCAUUUGUUGUUGAACUGACCUGACAUGUGUAUAGUAAUCUCAUGAACAAGAAAGAAUGUGUUCACACGUUUGCUUAAAUUGAAUUUAGCAAUCGCAUUAGGAUACUGAUAUUUCCACAAUGUAUAUACACUAUCCUUUUAAAUUUAACUUAUUUGCUUUUUAGACGGAAGCUCCUCAGUCUUAGAGAGUUCUGAAGGUGGAUUUCUCAGCCACGUUCAACCUGAUGAGUUCACUGCUUCUUCCCCAAACAUUGCAGAGCUGCAGGUAGGUGGGCUGAGUGGCUUCUGCAAGGGUGGCCCGCCAGGUUCCCCUGAGGGAGACCUGAGAAGCUCACCUUUUCAUCCUGGGGAAGUGAGAUUCGGAGUGGGUGUCAAGAGAUGGUUGCAUCUUCUUGACAAGAACAGAAAAUUAAGAUGAUUCCAAAUGUCUCUUUAUUUCCUGAGGUUCAGCCUUUCAAACAGAGACUUUCUUUUAUAGAUUUAAGUUGGUUGCAUUUAGCACAUAGUCAAACAGGAUUAAUAUUUUUCAUGGCUUAAGAGUUUCCCAAGUCAAAGUUUCAUUUUUUAUCAUUUUGAUUUACAGUUCUCAAUUGACAUUAAUAGACUCGAAGGCACGAAUAGCAAACAUAUUUCUAAGCCCUAGCUAGUGGUCCACUUGUAACAUGCUAUAUUUUACAAAAAAUGUCAAUAAAAUGAAAUUAUUUUCUCUACGGCAGGAAAUUUGGGCUGUGAACUUACGUGUGAUGUAAGUAGGCACCUGGCGGGGAAGUCUGGGAACACAGGUCCCGCUUGUUUUCUGUUCUCCCGAGAAAAACCCACAUUCUGUUCUGCCCUUUUCAACAUCUUCAGUGGGGGGACGAGUGGGAACAUUUUUCUUGGGAUUUUAUUUUGUUUGGGGAUCCAGCUAAUGGGUUUGCCUGGAAGCCUCAGGGCUAAUGAUCUGCAUUUAGAAACAGUGCCACAGUCAUGGCAGGUGUUAUUUGUAUGUUAUUUGUAUGUCUCUGUGUGUUAUUUGUAUCAGGUGUUGAAUGUGGCGGUUGUCACUGUGGCCACCCUGACCCCAGAGCAAACAUAUAAGUGGGAGAUAACCACUUUAAUAAAACACAAAACAUGGUCCAAA